GUCGCGUGACGUCAUCUCCGUGAGCAGGAUUGGCCCUGGAACAGUGUGGGGCCUGGACCGCUGGGUAGGCGCGUCCAGCGGCCUGAGCAGGGGAGGGUAAUGAGGCUGUUACGCGCCUUCUCCGCAUCUUGGCGGGAGCCUGACGCCCCGCUUCUUCCCUAACGGGGUGUUCCACCGGCGCCUGCCGAGGCCUAGGCCUCCGCAGCCGCCCUCCGUCUCCUCAGCCCCGACGCUGCGCCCGCUUUGUGCGCAUUUUUCUCUGGGGAAACUGAGGCUCCGAGUGCGAAAGUCAGCCGAGGUCGCCCCGCCCAGGACAGAGAAGGGCUGGGGGUCGGCUGAGCCGCGGCAUUCCCGGGCCCCGCUAGGGCUGCAGGGUCUCAGGAUGGCAGCCUCGGCGCAGGUGUCUGUGACCUUUGAGGAUGUGGCUGUGACAUUCACCCAGGAGGAGUGGGGACAGUUGGAUGCAGCCCAGAGAACCUUGUAUCAGGAGGUGAUGCUGGAGACCUGCGGACUUCUCAUGUCUCUGGGCUGUCCUUUGUUCAAACCAGAGCUGAUCUACCAGUUGGAUCACAGACAGGAGCUAUGGAUGGCUACAAAAGACCUCUCCCAAAGCUCCUAUCCAGGUGACAACACAAAACCCAAGACCACAGAGCCUACCUUUUCUCACCUGGCCUUGCCUGAGGAAGUCUUACUCCAGGAACAACUGACACAAGGAGCCUCAAAGAACUCCCAAUUAGGGCAAUCCAAGGAUCAGGAUGGGCCAUCUGAAAUGCAAGAAGUCCACUUGAAAAUAGGGAUAGGCCCCCAGCGGGGGAAGCUGCUGGAGAAAAUGAGUUCUGAACGUGAUGGUUUGGGGUCAGAUGAUGGUGUAUGUACAAAGAUUACACAGAAACAAGUUUCAACAGAAGGUGAUCUCUAUGAAUGUGAUUCACAUGGACCAGUUACAGAUGCCUUGAUUCGCGAAGAGAAAAAUUCCUAUAAAUGUGAGGAAUGCGGGAAAGUGUUUAAAAAGAAUGCCCUCCUUGUUCAGCAUGAACGGAUUCACACUCAAGUGAAGCCCUAUGAAUGCACAGAGUGUGGGAAAACCUUUAGCAAGAGCACUCAUCUUCUUCAGCACCUCAUCAUCCACACUGGGGAGAAGCCCUAUAAGUGCAUGGAGUGUGGGAAGGCUUUUAACCGCAGGUCACACCUCACACGGCACCAGCGGAUUCACAGUGGAGAGAAGCCUUAUAAGUGCAGUGAAUGUGGAAAGGCCUUCACCCACCGCUCCACUUUUGUCUUGCAUCACAGGAGCCACACUGGAGAAAAACCCUUUGUGUGCAAAGAGUGUGGCAAAGCCUUUCGAGAUAGGCCAGGUUUCAUUCGACACUACAUCAUCCACACGGGAGAGAAGCCCUAUGAGUGCAUUGAGUGUGGGAAGGCCUUCAACCGCCGGUCAUACCUCACGUGGCACCAACAGAUUCACACUGGAGUGAAACCCUUUGAAUGCAACGAGUGUGGAAAAGCUUUUUGCGAGAGUGCAGACCUCAUUCAACACUACAUUAUCCACACUGGGGAGAAGCCCUAUAAGUGCAUGGAGUGUGGGAAGGCGUUCAACCGUAGGUCACACCUCAAGCAGCAUCAACGGAUUCACACUGGGGAGAAGCCUUAUGAAUGCAGUGAAUGUGGAAAGGCCUUCACCCACUGCUCCACUUUUGUCUUGCAUAAAAGGACCCACACAGGAGAAAAACCCUAUGAAUGCAAAGAAUGUGGAAAAGCCUUUAGUGAUAGGGCAGACCUCAUUCGCCACUUCAGCAUCCACACUGGAGAGAAACCCUAUGAGUGCGUGGAGUGUGGAAAGGCCUUCAACCGCAGCUCACACCUCACGAGGCACCAACAGAUUCACACUGGAGAGAAACCCUAUGAAUGCAUCCAGUGUGGGAAAGCCUUUUGCCGGAGCGCAAACCUUAUUCGACACUCCAUCAUUCACACUGGAGAGAAGCCGUAUGAAUGCAGUGAGUGUGGAAAGGCUUUUAAUCGCGGCUCAUCCCUCACACAUCAUCAAAGGAUUCAUACUGGGAGAAACCCUACCAUUGUAACAGAUGUGGGAAGACCUUUUAUGACUGCACAGACUUCAGUCAACAUCCAGGAACUUUUAUUAGGGAAAGAGUUUUUGAAUAUCACCACUGAAGAAAAUCUGUGGUGAAAGGGAACAUCUUACCAUCUGGCCAUUCACACUGAAGAGAAACUUCAUAAGCAUCCUCUCUUUGAGAAAACGUGUAAUAGAUGAUCAUUUGUCGUCUAAACAAUCAAGUUAGAAAUUGAACCAGCCUGGAGUCUUAUUCUCCACCUGAGAAUUCACCCAUGAGAGAGACCCAGUGGUUGCUAUGCACUUAGGAAAACUUUCAGCCACAUCUUUCUUCUUAGUUUACAGUGAAAUAUUAUCUCAGGGAUAUUUUUUUUUUUUUUUUGAGACGGAGUCUCGCUCUGUCGCCCAGGCUGGAGUGCAGUGGCGGGAUCUCGGCUCACUGCAAGCUCCGCCUCCCGGGUUCACGCCAUUCUCCUGCCUCAGCCUCCCAAGUAGCUGGGACUACAGGCACCCGCCACUACGCCUGGCUAAUUUUUUGUAUUUUUAGUAGAGACGGGGUUUCACCGUUUUAGCCGGGAUGGUCUCGAUCUCCUGACCUCGUGAUCCGCCCGCCUCAGCCUCCCAAAGUGCUGGGAUUACAGGCGUGAGCCACCGCGCCCGGCCAUCUCAGGGAUAUUUAAACAAAGGAAGAGGAAAUAUAGGGAAGAGAAAGAAACCACAGCUUCUUUUAGACUUGUCUGACAAGCCUAUGGCAAUUUUGUCGUCCCUUUGUUAUUUUAUGUGGGAGAGGGAAAUGUUUCAGAAACGAAAGAUCUCAUCCCCUUUAUUUUUCUGUGUAUGCAUUCACUGCUGCCCAGUGUCAGAACAGUUAUACAAACGAGGGCUUGAAAACAUUUUGUGAAAACUUGCUUAGUCCUGCAACGUUCUCCACUCUCGAGGUGCAGAAGCAUACAUCUUUAUAAAAAAUAUGGAGGCUUGAGUUAUGAAACACUUUUAUAAGGAGAUAAGGAUGUACAUAUGUUUGGACACAUUGUCCACUUCAGAUGCUUGUUUAAAAAAAUGUUUCACCAUGUGUCUUUACCCAAUACACAUACUUUUUCUUGAUGUGGAUUUACUUUUUUUUUUUUUUUUUAAGUUUUCCUGGGAUAGGGAUGAUAGUGUAAUUGUUCAUGCCCACAGUAAUCCUGGGAAUCUUAGUUUUUUCCUAUGAUUGUGGUUUCUCAGCUUCUUUACCUCUCCUUUGAGUUAGGUCCACCUCAGUUUUCUAAAGGUCAAAUUAAGGCCCCCCCAAAAAUACAGUAUGUAGCUGAAUUCCUUUGAAAGAUCAUGAUAAACUCAGAAGAACAAACAUAGAAGGAAUGUCAUUUUUAAUCUUUUUAAAGAGUGUGUGAAAAUUCACUUUAACUGGAAUUUUAACAGGCAAGCCGGCAUGCAUAUAUGUAGGGAUGUGUGACUUUCACAGUUGUCACCAUGGACUUAGGCUUGAUUAAAAUGCUACACAUUUAGAGCGUUUUGUAAUUCCUUUUUUAUAUUUUUAAGACUAGAUUUUGAGCCAUGUGAUAGUUUUACCUCAUAUUAAAUAUAUUGUACAGAAGUAAAAAUAAUCAUGUAUUCACUUUGAA